AGAAGUCGCUUAGCUCUUCGGUGGUUGUCCCACGUCCGGAGGCCUAGCCGUCGCUUACCUAGGAUGCCGCGUGGAAGCCGAAGCCGCACCUCCCGCAUGGCCCCUCCGGCCAGCCGGGCCCCUCAGAUGAGAGCUGCACCCAGGCCAGCACCAGUCGCUCAGCCACCAGCAGCGGCACCCCCAUCUGCAGUUGGCUCUUCUGCUGCUGCGCCCCGGCAGCCAGGUCUGAUGGCCCAGAUGGCAACCACUGCAGCUGGCGUGGCUGUGGGCUCUGCUGUGGGGCACACAUUGGGUCACGCCAUUACUGGGGGCUUCAGUGGAGGAAGUAAUGCUGAGCCUGCGAGGCCUGACAUCACUUACCAGGAGCCUCAGGGAACCCAGCCAGCACAGCAGCAGCAGCCUUGCCUCUAUGAGAUCAAACAGUUUCUGGAGUGUGCCCAGAACCAGGGUGACAUCAAGCUCUGUGAGGGUUUCAAUGAGGUGCUGAAACAGUGCCGACUUGCAAACGGUAGGAUUGGCCUAAUGAAGAAGUUCAACCUGGAGAGAUGGAAAAUCAGCUCUCAUAACUAAGUUAAUUUAGUAUAAAAAUAGAAUUGAUAGUGAGGGUAUAAAGUGUAACCAUCAGUUAAACCUCUCCUGUCAUUCCUGGCUUCCUUGCUUCAGAAUUGAAAUGGAAGUGGGGGUGUCCCUACUCUGUAGAAUCUGGGACUGGGCAAAUGUUUGUGUGGCCUCCUUAAACUAGCUGUUAUGUUAUGAUUUUAUUCUUUGUGAGUUAAUUAGAAUAAAGUCAUUUUCUUCCAA